GUAGUGGCCACAGCCUUACAGGCAGGCAGGGGUGGUUGGUGUCAACAGGGGGGCCAACAGGGUACCAGAGCCAAGACCCUCGGCCUCCUCCCCCGCCGCCUUCCUGCAGGUAACAGGGAGCCCUGCGCUGCGCCCCCAGUCCUUGCAGGACUGCGCCGUGGGGGAAGGGGCCGGGCGGGGAGGAGGCGGCGGGCGCGCGCCCCGCUCGCGGGUCUGCGCUCUGGGGCCCGCGCGGGAGCGAGCUCGGCGCGGCGCCGGCGGCCGGUUGAGCUGUGCUCUCAGCUUCGGAGCAGCCUCCCCUUGCUGAUUGUGGGGCGCCCUGUAAUCUGCGCUUCGCGGGCGGCCCCCGACGGGUGAGGCGCCCGCGGCCAGAGCUCUCCAAGGCGGCCGCGGAGUCGGUCCUCGCAGGGAGGUGUGGAAGAUCUGCUUGGCUUUGAGGAAGAGUGGCAGUACUGCCUCACUGCAUAAGGGAUGGGAUCAGAGAACAGUGCUUUAAAGAGCUAUACACUGAGAGAACCACCAUUUACCUUACCCUCUGGACUUGCUGUUUAUCCCGCUGUACUGCAAGAUGGCAAAUUUGCUUCAGUUUUUGUGUAUAAGAGAGAAAAUGAAGACAAGGUUAAUAAAGCUGCCAAGCAUUUGAAGACACUUCGUCACCCUUGCUUGCUAAGAUUUUUAUCUUGUACUGUGGAAGCGGAUGGCAUUCAUCUUGUCACUGAGCGAGUACAGCCCCUGGAAGUGGCUUUGGAAACAUUGUCUUCUGCAGAGGUCUGUGCUGGGAUCUAUGACAUAUUGCUGGCUCUUAUCUUCCUUCAUGACAGAGGACACCUAACACACAAUAAUGUCUGUUUAUCAUCUGUGUUUGUGAGUGAAGAUGGACACUGGAAGCUAGGAGGAAUGGAAACUGUUUGUAAAGUUUCUCAGGCCACACCAGAGUUUCUGAGGAGUAUUCAGUCAAUAAGAGACCCAGCAUCUAUCCCUCCUGAAGAGAUGUCUCCAGAAUUCACAACUCUCCCAGAGUGUCAUGGACAUGCCCGGGAUGCCUUUUCAUUUGGAACAUUGGUGGAAAGUUUGCUCACAAUCUUAAAUGAACAGGUUUCAGCGGAUGUUCUCUCCAGCUUUCAACAGACCUUGCACUCAACUUUGCUGAAUCCCAUUCCAAAAUGUCGGCCAGCGCUCUGCACCUUACUAUCUCAUGACUUCUUCAGAAAUGAUUUUCUGGAAGUUGUGAAUUUCUUGAAAAGUUUAACAUUGAAGAGUGAAGAGGAGAAAACGGAAUUCUUUAAAUUUCUGCUGGACAGAGUCAGCUGCUUGUCAGAGGAAUUGAUAGCUUCAAGGUUGGUGCCUCUUCUGCUUAAUCAGUUGGUGUUUGCAGAGCCAGUGGCUGUUAAGAGUUUUCUUCCUUAUCUGCUUGGCCCCAAAAAAGAUCAUGCGCAGGGAGAAACUCCUUGCUUGCUCUCACCAGCCCUGUUCCAGUCACGGGUGAUCCCCGUGCUUCUCCAGUUGUUUGAAGUUCAUGAAGAGCAUGUGCGGAUGGUGCUGCUGUCUCACAUCGAGGCCUACGUGGAGCACUUCACUCAGGAGCAGCUGAAGAAAGUCAUCUUGCCACAGGUUUUGCUGGGCCUGCGUGAUACUAGCGAUUCCAUUGUGGCAAUUACUCUGCAUAGCCUAGCAGUGCUGGUCUCUCUGCUUGGACCAGAGGUGGUUGUGGGAGGAGAACGAACCAAGAUCUUCAAACGCACUGCCCCAAGUUUUACUAAAAAUACUGACCUUUCUCUAGAAGAUUCUCCUAUGUGUGUCGUCUGCAGCCAUCACAGUCAGAUCUCGCCAAUCUUGGAGAACCCCUUCUCUAGCAUAUUCCCUAAAUGUUUCUUUUCUGGCAGCACGCCCAUCAACAGCAAGAAGCACAUACAGCGAGAUUACUACAAUACUCUUUUACAGACAGGCGAUCCAUUUUCUCAGCCUAUUAAAUUUCCCAUAAAUGGACUCUCAGAUGUAAAAAAUACUUCGGAGGACAGUGAAAACUUCCCAUCAAGUUCUAAAAAGUCUGAGGAGUGGCCUGACUGGAGUGAACCUGAGGAGCCUGAAAAUCAAACUGUCAACAUACAGAUUUGGCCUAGAGAACCUUGUGAUGAUGUCAAGUCCCAGUGCACUACCUUGGAUGUGGAAGAGUCAUCUUGGGAUGACUGCGAGCCCAGCAGCUUAGAUACUAAAGUAAACCCAGGAGGUGGAAUCACUGCUACAAAACCUGUUACCUCAGGGGAGCAGAAGCCUAUUCCUGCUUUGCUUUCACUCACUGAAGAGUCUAUGCCUUGGAAAUCAAGCUUACCCCAAAAGAUUAGCCUUGUACAAAGGGGGGAUGACGCAGACCAAAUCGAGCCGCCAAAAGUGUCAUCACAAGAAAGGCCCCUUAAGGUUCCAUCAGAACUUGGUUUAGGAGAGGAAUUCACCAUUCAAGUAAAAAAGAAGCCAGUAAAAGAUCCUGAGAUGGAUUGGUUUGCUGAUAUGAUCCCAGAAAUUAAGCCUUCUGCUGCUUUUCUUAUAUUACCUGAACUGAGGACAGAAAUGGUCCCAAAAAAGGAUGAUGUCUCCCCAGUGAUGCAGUUUUCCUCAAAAUUUGCUGCAGCAGAAAUUACUGAGGGAGAGGCUGAAGGCUGGGAAGAAGAAGGGGAGCUGAACUGGGAAGAUAAUAACUGGUGACAAUAGAUGUGAGUUAAACUUUAGGAAAAAGGAUUCCCUUUUUUUAAAAAAAAUCAAUACCUCAAAAGCAGGCUUUGGGACAAGAAAACCCCAAAGUGGCCUGCUUUUCCCAUCCCAGGAGCUCAUUAUCCAGUCUGUGCCAACUGAAGUAGGAGACUGACUGUGAGUGCUGGCUAAAAGCCCUGGGUGGUGAGGCUCACAGUACUGGUUUCCAGGAGGAAGAGCCUUUGUGCAUUUGACUGAGGCCAGUUUCUAUGAAGAGCAAGUAGCUGAGGAGAGGUCGAAUUUACUGCUUUUUCCAGGACAAUUCUGGAAGUAAAGAAAAUGUAAUUCAAGCUGGUUAGCUUAAUUUUGUGCCAUUCUUUAACAUAAGAGUAAGCUCUAUUAUGAAAUACAACUUUAAAAAAUUUUAGCUAUAAAUUAUAUAAAUGAUUUUAAAUUGCUGAGGUUUCCUUAGGCAGCUUAUUUAUUUGUUUACAGUUAGACUAUCUGAGUAAAUGGUUCUUUGUGGACCUAGGCAGUUCCUGACUGUUCCACAUGUAGUACAUUGUACCAAAGUUCUUAAUAAGAAUAUUCCCCACAAUCCUGUUCUCUAAAUGUCAAAUAAAGAUUAUUUUCACUAGAUUCAACUUUACAAAAUUUGUUUUAUAUCUGUUAGAAAAUGUACAGACAUAAGUAUUUUCAGUUGACAAAGCAUCAAACCCAGUUCUGCCUAGUGAUAAGUUUCACCCUAGAGUAUGUAUGUAACGUUUUAGCUUAUCCAUCCUUUCUUGGAGCGCCUCCAUUUCCAUUGAAAGCCAGGCUGGAGCAGGACCCUUUUGGAGUAGUGACUCAGUUGCUUCCAAAGCCCCUGCUAUUGUAUGCAGCGCUGACCUGUACUCUUCUUCCCAGGGGAACUCCUGACGAGCUCUUUUUGCAUAAGGCUGGAAAAAAAACAUAAGUAAUAUCACAAUAUCCAUUCUAAAUAUAAAGAACCUUCCUUUUGGACUGGAGUAAAGCUUACAUGCAAAUUUUAUUCUAGUCAUUGGAUCACAAGGGUAGGAGGAUGCACCCCAAAACCCCUACACAGUCAUCUAGAAAAAUAUGUAAAGGCAUUUUGGUUUAUCAUAGCAAUUCAGAGUGCUACUACCAGUGUCUUAGUUUGUAUGUGGUAUACAACAAGUAUCCUGUCCCAAAGGGCUCCCAAUGAGAAGUGCUGCAUAGUCCAAGCUUACAUGUCUUAUAAACAAGUUCAUAAAUGUAUUUUCUUUUUAUGAGAGUUUGACUAAAACUUAUCAGAAUGUUGUUCUUCAUGAAUUACUACUAUACUAAUUACUAUACUAAUAGUGCUCAAAACAAUAUUUUGAAUAUCCUUAUUGGUGUCAAAUUCUGCCUUUUAAUAAGUAGAUGUGAUCUUCAGUUACUGCCAAAAAUUAUUAGGAGACUCAUUUGAUUAAUAAGGCAAGGAAUCAAACUAAACAUUUAGGAGUAAGUUUCUUUCAUUUUCUUCUGUGGUUCAGUAAAGACUGCAUUUAUAGCAUCACUGGUACAAUAUGUAACUUCCCUUAAAGGUUACUACCAAUAAUUCAAACAUACUGAAAGAAUAUAUUUGAUAUGGUGUAGUCCCACUUCUUAAUUUUAAAAGCAACUACCAUAAAACAGAAUUUUACAUGUCUAGAUCUAUUUGAUUUGAAAUUCAGCAUAAGGCUGGAAACCACACUGGUUUGUUUCGUCAGUAAGUAAAAAGGGCAGAAUUUGCCUUGUUAAAGUUUGGCCCCUAUUGAAAUCAGCCCAUACCUGUAAAGAUGACCUCUUUGCUUCUUCUACAGUCACAUUAGCAAAGGGUUCCCAGAAAAUACCUUUUUCCUGUUUCACACGUUCCACUUUGGCAGCUUCAGUUUCAUCUACAAACCCAGUCUGCCAGGGACCAUGAAAAACCAAGCAAAUAGCAACAUGUUAGCACUCUACUAGAUAUGAAAUGGCCACAUAAUUUAAGUGCUGAGUGUUCAACCAUACUAGGCAAAUUCUGGAAGUCACAUGGACUGAUCUAUAAAUACUCUUAGUAUAAUCUGGAUUAAAUCACUCUACUGUGUUCUUCCUUACAAAAUAGUUAGUUAUAGAGUUGUCUUUGCAGGAAAAAAUGAUAGUCUGCUAACCUUUACUGUAUAAGCUAAGAAACUGGCAACAGCAGUGUAUACACAUGUACUUAAAAUCCAGCUUAGAUGUAAUAUAAGUAGGCCAAGUGUGGUGGCUCAUGCCUCUAAUCCCAGGACUUUGGUGGGAGGAAUGCUUGAGCCCAGGAGUUUGAGGUUAUAGCGAGCUAUGAUCACACCACCACACUCCAAUCUGGGCGACAGAGCGAGACUCUGUCUAAAAAAUAAAGUUCAGUGAGUCAAGUGGGCCCAUUUCACCUAAAAAAAUAUAUAUGUAAUAUAUGUAAAAUAUAUAACGUGCAUCAUUACAUGUAAUAUAUCAAAUAAUUCAGUUUCUCCUGGUAGUCUAAAUUUGUGGUUUAACAGUUCCACUAGUAUUUCAAUUAACUAUUAUUUCCUCACACUAAGUUCCCAAGUAUGCAUAGACAUAGGAACCUUGUGAUUCAAAAUUUUGGUUUUAAUUGUAAAAACAGGUCUUGGCUGCAAAGAGAAUAAAAAAGCCAUGCCAAAAAAAAAAAAAAAAAAAAAAAAAAAAGGGCCCUGAGCUUACCCUGGCUUGGGAGGCUGCCCAAAUAAAAAAAAAAAAAAAAAAAAAAAAAAGCCAUGCCUAAAUUAUACCCAAAAUAUGGUAGUAAACAUCCUCUCAGGCCUACCUAAUUAUGUGAUCAAGUGUAUUUAAUUAUGAUUAUUAAUAGCUUAGGGAUCCUCAUUAGUCAUCUCACUGCCUGGAUAAUCAGUGCUAUUACACCCCAAACUACAGGCAGAGGAACUACAAGUGUCCUUUUUUGAGACAGUCUCACUCUGUCGCUCAGGCUGGAGUGCAGUGGCAUGAUCUUGGCUUACUGCAAUCUCUACCUCCCCAGUUCAAGCAAUUCUCCUGCCUCAGCCUCCCGAGUAGCUGGGACUGCAGGCGCGUACCACCAUGCCCGGCUAAUUUUUGUAUUUUUAGUAGAAACAGGGUUUCCCCAUGUUGGCCAGGCUGGUCUUGAACUCCUGACCUCAUGAUCCACCCACCUUGGCCUCCCAAAGUGCUGGGAUUACAGGCAUGAGCCGCCGCGCCUGGCCCCAAGUGUUUUACUUCUGUGGCCUCAAUUGCUUAGUAAAAGUCGUCAGCACUGUGCUCAGCACUGUGAAAAGUUUAAGCUAAGAAGACACUCAGGUUGGUUACAGUUACAUAAUUUCGGAAAAAAAAAAAUAGGACAAAGAAUAAAACAUGAGCCAUGUAAAGAAAGUACCUUCUCCAGAAAGGAUACAACUUUGUUCUUAGUUUCUUCAGAACUGAGACACUGUGGAACUAUCUCUUCAUGAUUUGUUCCCUAUUAAAAAAUUGAUGAACAAGACCAAUUUUAACAUUUCAACAACUUGCAAAGACAAAUAGAUGAGUUUUAUGAGCUACCUUAACCAAAAAUUCAUUUUAAGUAAGAGUCCCAGAGGAUCCUCAAAGGUGAUAAACUCAUGAUUCCUUCAGGGUCCCUAAGGAUAAUACAAAAUUAACUUCUGUACAAGUGUUGUAAGCUUUAAUUACUUCUGCUGGGUCAUACUAAUGCUUCUGGACUCCCUUAUGAUCAUAGGCAUGACUAUACAGCAAAUGCAGUAAGAGUAAAGGAGCAACCCAUCUUACAGGUUUAGGUUCAUCAGCCUAACCCUUAUGACUGAUAGCACAAAAUGAAAUGUAUUAUCAUUUGACCCAAAAAUACUAUCUGCUGGAAGACUGUGUCUGUGUCUGUCUGUAUCAGUAGGCCUGCUGUGUAUGCCUGUUCUGGUCCUUGUUUAUUCAGAGGACCUUACGAAAUUCACUUCAUUUAUCUAAGCCUCAUUUUGAGAAGCUGUAAAAGAGAUAACGAGUAAUGUACCCUUCAGACAAUUUUCCGAUUGCAAUACAGAAGCAGUUCAAUAAAUGUUUUGGGAUUGUUCUGGAAUAUUUGAAAUAUUAAAAUGGUUUGAAAGUCA